CUCAUUUCCUCCCAGCCUCGUGCGGGAAAUGGCUUUAAUUCUGACGGCAGGGCUGUGAGGGACUAGCGGGAACCCGAGCCUUUUGUCAAGGAACUGCGGCGUCGGUGGCCAGUCAUCCCCGCCGCCGCGGAGCCGCUGCACUGCUGGGGGAUCUCCCAGCAGCUCUGACGAGCGCGGGCUGCAGCAUGGGCAGAAAACGCUGCCCUGCAGAUUAGCUGGGUGGAUUUUUUAAGCGCACCCCACCCCCCAAACCCAUAAAAUAACAAAACCAACCCGCAGUGGCCGACCGGAGAUAGCUAAGAUGCCGCGCAGGAGUUUCCACCUGGAUGUUUGAGGUUGUGUAGAUGUGGCCGGCACCCUUGAGAGUGGAGCUAGGGGGUGCAGACUGAGCAGUGAACAGAAGGAGCCUUGGACAGGGCUGGGCCAGCCUCCCGAGUUCCAGGAGCGAAUUGCAAACCCACCGGGAAAAUGAGCGAAGAGACGGUCCCCGAGGCUGCCUCGCCGCCGCCCCCGCAGGGGCAGCCUUACUUUGACCGCUUCUCAGAGGACGACCCCGAGUACAUGCGCCUUCGCAACCGGGCGGCGGACCUGCGGCAGGACUUCAACCUGAUGGAGCAGAAGAAGCGCGUCACCAUGAUCCUGCAGAGUCCCUCUUUCAGGGAGGAGCUGGAAGGCCUCAUCCAGGAGCAGAUGAAGAAGGGGAACAACUCCUCCAACAUCUGGGCCCUGCGACAGAUCGCGGACUUCAUGGCCAGCACCUCCCACGCAGUCUUCCCGACAUCUUCCAUGAAUGUCUCCAUGAUGACGCCUAUCAAUGACCUCCACACAGCUGACUCCCUGAACCUGGCCAAAGGGGAGCGGCUCAUGCGGUGCAAGAUCAGCAGUGUCUACCGACUCCUGGACCUCUAUGGCUGGGCCCAGCUGAGUGACACCUAUGUCACGUUGAGAGUCAGCAAGGAGCAGGACCACUUCCUGAUCAGCCCUAAGGGAGUUUCUUGCAGUGAAGUCACAGCGUCCAGCCUGAUCAAGGUGAACAUUCUGGGAGAGGUGGUGGAGAAGGGCAGCAGCUGCUUCCCAGUGGACACCACAGGCUUCUGUCUGCACUCGGCCAUCUAUGCAGCGAGGCCCGACGUGCGCUGCAUCAUCCACCUGCACACACCGGCCACAGCAGCGGUGUCGGCCAUGAAGUGGGGCCUCCUGCCUGUCUCCCACAAUGCCCUGCUGGUGGGGGACAUGGCCUAUUAUGACUUCAAUGGGGAAAUGGAGCAGGAAGCCGAUCGGAUCAACCUGCAGAAGUGCCUUGGACCCACCUGCAAGAUCCUGGUGCUAAGAAACCAUGGAGUGGUUGCUCUGGGUGACACGGUAGAGGAGGCAUUUUACAAGAUCUUCCACCUGCAGGCUGCAUGUGAGAUACAGGUGUCGGCUCUGUCCAGUGCCGGGGGAGUGGAGAACCUCAUCCUCCUGGAGCAGGAGAAGCACCGGCCCCAUGAGGUGGGCUCCGUGCAGUGGGCCGGGAGCACCUUUGGGCCUAUGCAGAAGAGUCGGCUGGGGGAGCAUGAGUUUGAGGCCCUCAUGAGGAUGCUGGACAACCUGGGCUACAGAACAGGUUACACGUAUCGCCACCCCUUUGUUCAAGAGAAAACCAAACACAAAAGUGAGGUGGAGAUUCCAGCCACGGUCACAGCCUUCGUGUUUGAGGAGGACGGUGCCCCGGUGCCCGCCCUGCGACAGCAUGCCCAGAAGCAGCAGAAGGAGAAGACCCGCUGGCUCAAUACGCCCAACACCUACCUGCGGGUCAAUGUGGCCGAUGAGGUCCAGAGGAGCAUGGGCAGCCCCCGACCCAAGACCACGUGGAUGAAGGCUGACGAGGUGGAGAAAUCCAGCAGUGGCAUGCCGAUUCGCAUCGAAAACCCAAACCAAUUUGUGCCUCUCUAUACUGACCCCCAGGAAGUACUGGAGAUGAGGAACAAGAUUCGAGAACAAAACCGACAAGAUGUGAAGUCAGCGGGGCCUCAGUCCCAGCUCCUGGCGAGCGUCAUUGCCGAGAAGAGCCGAAGCCCGUCUACAGAGAGCCAGCUGAUGUCCAAGGGAGACGAGGAUACCAAAGACGAUUCAGAGGAGACGGUGCCCAACCCCUUCAGCCAACUCACUGACCAGGAGUUGGAGGAGUACAAGAAAGAGGUGGAGAGGAAGAAACUAGAACUUGAUGAGACAGGACAGGAACGAGAGCCAGGCUCUGGUCCGGCCGUGUGCGAGUUCUUCAGCGUUGCCCUCCACAUCUGGAGUAACAUAUUGGAGAGAAAGAAACUGCCCCAGAAGAGCCUGGCUCACCUGCAAAGUCUGCACCUGCUUCUCCAGUGCAGAGCCCAGCGAAGGAGGCAGAGACAAAGAGCCCUUUAGUCUCUCCUUCCAAGUCUUUAGAGGAAGGUACUAAGAAGACAGAAACAAGCAAAGCCGCCACCACAGAGCCCGAAACAACCCAGCCGGAAGGGGUGGUGGUCAACGGGAGGGAGGAGGAGCAGACGGCAGAGGAAAUCCUCAGCAAAGGCCUGAGCCAGAUGACCACCAGUGCUGACACGGAUGUUGAUACCUCUAAGGACAAAACCGAGUCGGUCACCAGCGGCCCCAUGUCCCCAGAGGGCUCACCUUCCAAGUCUCCCUCAAAGAAGAAAAAGAAAUUCCGAACCCCCUCCUUCCUGAAAAAGAGCAAAAAGAAGGAGAAAGUGGAGUCCUGAUUCAUGACACCCUUGGGCUCCCUCCUGCCUCCUCUCUCUCCUCCCCUUCCCUUCUCCCAUCUCUGUCCCUGCAAGCACAGGGCUAAGGAGGGAUAGAGUAGGACCCUGGACCACAUUCGGAAGGGGAACUUAGAGAUCACCCGACCAACCCUUCGUUUUACAGUUGCCCAAGAGAAAUCAGGUGACUUGCCCAAGGUCACACAGCUAGUUAGCGGCAGAGCCUGCACUCGAAUUCAGGUCUCCUGACUUCCAGUCCAGUGCUCCUUCUACUACACAACACUGCCUAGUUGUGGGCUGCCUUUGUUUGGAUGCUGUCCACCAAUCUGAGCCUAGGGCAAGAAGGCCAGAAAUGGGCCGUGAGCUCUCACAGGCUCAGACUAAAUCAGAGGUCAAGGCUUCCCCUGAGUAAGGUCCAUUUCUUCCCAGGAAUCCAAUCUCCUGUGGAUGGAGCUAUCUCUACAUUUAAAAAUCUCUUCUCUUUUCCACUUUGGGUCCCUGCCCUGCUGCUCAAAGUGACUAGCCAAAUUGACCCCUCCAACAGAAAGUAAUCUUUGUUCCCAAGGGCUGAUGGCUUAGCUUGUACUACCCCAAACAUUAACCCUGAGCUUUCUUCAUGGAACCUCUUGAAUGAUGGAUGGAAGAGCUAUAAGAGGUGGUAGGCAUAGGGGCAAGCCAUGUAAGCUGAGGAUUGGGGAUGGUUUCAUCAACAUAAGAGGCCAGGAACUUGACCCCUUUGAAUUGUGCAUCUCAGGCACUUCAAAACUAAAACCAAAUUUAGCAUAGGAAAAAGUUGUUUAAUGCUCAGGGCAGAAAUUUGGGGAAGUUGAAAUCCUCUGUUGGCUUUGGGUUGUAUAAGGAGGAUCAAAACAACAGAGGAAAUGCUGACUUUCUAGCUUUGCAUGACACCUGGAGCAAUGCACUGUACCUGCCUCACUCCUGUCCAGUGGUCAGGUUUCCCCUGACCUUCCCUCACCCCCAGAAACACUUGCUUACAGACCGAAACUGGCAUCUUACUCUUGGCACCUUGACUUGCACCCUCUGAGGUUCCAACUCAGUCAUUCUUUGUCCAGCAGAGGAGAAUCAGAAAUGAGCCCUUCAGGAUUAAUCCUCUUGCACCAGCUCUCAGAGAAAUGCUGGGUAUCCCUGUCCUUGUCCCUAUCUGUCCAUCCUGGGGCCUGGUAAUGGCCACAGUUAUUGUUUUAAAUGCCAACACUGUCUUCUCAUGUUCUUCCGUGGGGCAUUGAUUAAUGAGCAUUUGUUGGCUCCUAAAAAUUAGACAAUCCAUUCUCUUGAAAGCACCGUGUCUUGAAAGAAUAUUUUUCCUUUUGAUCUGACUAUCGUGAAAAUAUUUUUGAAAGUUCUUAAUCAUAGUUUUCCACUUUUGAGCACUUGCUAUCUAUAGACACUGUGCAGGCUUCACAUACAUUACAUUCUUUAACCCUCACAGUAAUCCUUUGAGGGGGGUAAGAUCAUUCCCAUUUUGUGGGUGAGGAAAUUGACCCCCUAAAAUGAUAAUUGACUUGUCCCAGCUGACUUGGCUAGAAAGAUCUGGAUCCUGGAUUUGAAUCCAGGUCAGUCUGAGUCCAGAGCCCUUGCUCUUAACAGCUAUGGUGAACAGACAACUUUAAUCCCCAGGGGUGGUGGUUUUCAUCCAGGAUUUGUCUCUAUGACUGUUCUCCAUUGCAUAAUGUUAGCACGUGAAGCAAAGGUAGGGAACACCCUGUGCUCAUCCUCAUCACUGCACGUGAAGUUCCUGGUCAAUGUGGACUGUGGUGAUGCUACUGUGUGCCUCUGACAAAGGAGAGGCAAGAGCCUUCUGGUUGGGGCGGGAAAUACCAUCCAUAGUUGGCUAUUUCUUGAGAAGGAAGGAAACUGACCUAGGACCAAGGUAAACCUGACACUGUGUCUCUCUAGUGCAGAUUCCUAACUGCUACCCCAGGCUCCAUCUCUGUUCUACUUCCUGAUUGGGUCAAAUUUUAGGAGGGACAACCCACUCAUGCCUCAGAAAAAUCUGUCAUAUGGGAAAUGCCUUUAAAAGCCAAUCCCUUGAUGCCUUCUUUUAAAAAGUAGAUUUCACACUUAUUCAUUUAUCCUUACAUGGUAUUUGUUAAGGAUCCACUGAGCACCAGGCAUUAUGCUGACGUUGAAAGAGAGCCAUCAUUAUGACUAGAAUAAUAAGUGGCAAACGAUGUUGUGAGAAUGGUGAACACGACCUCUGAUGCAGCCUUUUGUGUGCGAGUUGUUCUACUUCGGGGGUGAUGUUGAUUGCCUCUGCAUUCAACACACUCUAUUCCCUUGACAAUGAGGCCUCACUUAGGCCUCAUUGGGUGGAGUCUUGCUGCAGCAUUAUUCUGGGAAUUUAUGCCAUGGGCCCACUUUCUAUUGAUAGAUGAACCUGUCAGUUGGUUCAUUCCUCAUGCAUUCCAAAAACAUGCAUUGAGCUUGGGUCAAGGGCCAGGCAUGAGGAUAGGCAUAGUUCCUGCCCUCAAGAAGUUCAUGAGCAUAGGAGGUGUAUAGACAAAUUGCAAAACAGGCAAGGGUACCAAGGUGGCAUAAGAAAGCAUCAAUUAACUAUCUUGGGGACCAGAGAAACCCUGAGAGAAGCAAUGGCUGCUAAGGUUUUAAAACAAAGAGUAAAUUUCCAGUAGAAUGAAAGGAUUGGCAGGGCAUGCCACAAUGAGGGAAGAAUGUGCAAAGGUGUGGACGCAUGAAAUGCCAUGAUGGGUUCCGCUGAGCAACGUGGCAUUGCCAGAGCAUGAUGUGGAAGCUCAGGGGUUGAGGGGUCCCUUCAUAGGUAGGCAGGGCUGAAUCCUAAGGAAACUGGUAGGAAGUGUGGAGGAGCUAGACUUGUCAUGGAAGGGGUUUGGAGCCACUGGAGCCUUUAAAUCAGGAUAGAGUCAUGAUCAGAAUUGCAUUUUAGGAAAAUCCCUUUGGUGGCUGAAUGGAGACUGUGGACUGGAUGGGCGUGGGAUGGUGGCAUGGGAGCUAUGAGGCCUUUUUGAAAUGUCAAUACUAAAACAUAGUUGAUGGCCUGCUUUACACGAUGUUUCCUCUACAGCAGAUAGUGAGUUUCCAACACAAAAUUUAUUUCCAUAAAAGUCUUUGGAUAAAGCACCUUAAGAGGGAUUUUCAACAAGGAGAGGGGAGCAUUCAAAGAGCUAAUGUUUCCAGUUUUAUUUUGUCUUGGUGUAGAAUUGCUGGGAGAGGUGUCCAGCCAUCCUGCCAUUUCUUCUUCCCUUGCACAGAAUGUGGCACAUUUAGCUCCAGGCUUGAGGACAUGCACCAAAUGCUACAGAAACAGACAUGUGGUCCAAACAAAUCUACAGGCUAUUAGAAAGGAAAGGCCAUUUUCUUUGGCUGUGGAUAAAAGUUGGCUGAAAACUUUGACCAAUAUCUGACUGGAGAAAAUGUGUAUUCAAGAGCUCAGAUUUGGUGGGCAGUAGGUUCAUGUCUGGUUGAGCUACUGUGCUUGGAUGUGCCAGAGAAAAGGGUAACAUUUGAACCAAUGUGCUGCUCUGUGGCUGGCUGAGCUGGGAAGUGGAGAGGUUUCUGAGCUUAUUUCCAUCGCAAGGCAGGCAGGAGGAGAGAGGACAAGAAGGAUUAGUGGUUUCGCAGAGACAGGCUUGGCUCCAACGGCUCCUUGCGUAGUGUUGGCUGCACCCAACAGUGGUGUGAGAGAACCGUCCAUACCAUGUGACCUUCCUCCCAAACUGCAGAAAGAGACACCUUCUAGCCCAGAUCUGGACUCCCUAAGAGCCUCCUGGCCUGCAUGCAACCCAAGUAACUGUCCUACUUUGGCCAGUUGACCCCCUCCACUCUCCUAUAACUAAAACAGGGUUCUUCCUCUGUGAACAGAUAAGUUCUUUUUAAAGGACUUGGGGGAAAUUGGAUGAAGAGCAGUAAGUUCUUACAGUAAGAACCCCACUGUAAAGCACUGCCCUCUGCCACUGAUCCAUGUAGACUGAAUUUGAAUCCCAUUCCCUGUGGAUGAUACCGUCACUUGCUCAUGGUGACAUGGCAAGACAGUCAUUCAGAUGUUUGGCAUUGUUGUAGCAGGGCUACUGCUAGUGUGGGGGAAAAUGCUAUAAAUCCACUUCUUUGAUUGCCAUGGAUUUGAAAGAACCAUUUGCCCAACAGCAUGAUUCGCCUCUGAAAGUCUAAAAAUAAUUUUCAAUUUUUCCAUGAAGGUAUGUGGAGGGUAAACACACAGCCUACGCAUAGGUCUGCAUGACAUGUUUUUUCUUUUUCUUUCUUUUUUUUUUUUUUUUUUUUUUUUUUUAGACGGAGCUUUGCUCUUUGUUGCCCAGGCUGGAGUGCAGUGGUGCAAUCUUAGCUCACUGCAACCUCUGCCUCCCGGUUUUUCAAGCGAUUCUUCUGUCUCAGCCUCCCAAGUAGCUGGAAUUACAGGAGCCCGCCACCUUGCCCAGCUAAUUUUUGUAUUUUUAGUAGAGACGGGGUUUCACCAUGUUGGCCAGGCUGGUCUUGAACUCCUGACCUCGUGAUCCACCUGCCUCGGCUUCCCAAAGUGCUGGGAUUACAGGAAUGAGCCACUGUGCCAGCUGACACGUUUUUUCUUUUGUGUGAAUUUUAUGUUCUAGUUUUGGGACAAGGGUAAUCAGUUCUUGACUAGUGAACAAAUGAGAGAACAUUUACCCCUUACUCAUUUUACACAUGCAGGUCAGCAGAAGCCCUAGAGUUGGUUGGCACAGUCGCAGUUGACUGAGCAUAGAGGAAACAGGUCUUUUUACAUUCUCUCUCAUCACUGGAGCUCAGUUGAACUCUAAGACCUUAGCACUCAAAGAGUCUGAAAAGAAAUGAGGGAGAGGCUAAAUUUAAGCUCUCCACUCCCACAGAAAGGACAGGGCACCCUACAAUCUAAAAGCCAGUGAGGCAGCCUAUCAUCUGUUUCACAUCUGUUCUGAAAGGGAUAGUUUAAUGCAAGAAGUAAGAGGCCUGUAGUGACUGUAAACUCAUGAAAUGUGCACAUUGGUUAUCUGUGCACAUUUCCACUUGCACCAUAACAUAAGAAAGCGUACAUGGAGUGUAAUUACUUCCAGAAGCCCCGUCUAACCAACCUAUUCAGAUGUGGCACACUUUCUGUCAUAAAUGAGAGACCACACGUAGAGCUCGGUCACCAAGGAAUGCCCAACAUCCCUUUACCUCUCACAAUGAGCAGCCACGCUCACCGGGAAGCAGUGUGGGGACUUCAGUGGGGUGUCCCUUAGUGGAGAACACCUUUCAUCAUUUUUAUAGAGACAAUUCCCUUGAGAAUGUAGGCUUUUCAUCUUAGGAACAAUUAGGAAGAAUCUCCAGCUGGGAGUGUUCUUAUGUAUACAGAAACAAUGGGUCGCAUUGGUUCAUACUUAGGUGAUAUUAGGUUUGGCUAUAUUGAUGUUUGGUGCCACUUACCUUCUAGAUUUUCCCAAAAGUUGGGUCAUUGCUAUGGGAAAUUGGGGCCUGCAGAUGGGGGAGAAAUGAUCAUUAUUGGUGCAGGGAAGGGGUUCAGGCAGAGCUGGAGUCUGAGGCUCAGUGUGAGAAAGCACUGGCAGUUUUCUAGUAGAGUCAGGUCCUGGGCUCCUCUCCUCACCCACUGUGUCCCGAACUGAGGCCAGCUGUGAUCGGCAAAUUGCUUAUCUCUAGGUAGUUUAAAGAAAACGUAAGAGUUUGGGGGGUGGUGGGAGAAUAACUGUAGAAAGACCCUAAACUCUUCUCUCCCCCAGCAAAUUAUCUUGUAUAAUGUUUAAAAACCCAAAGGCCAGAUCUCCCCUUUUAACGUGAAUCAGAAGGAGGAUGGCAAUUGGACCAAGGGCAGAGUGGCCACACUUGAAACACAUUAUAAAAUGGGAAUAUAUUUCAGGGAACCCCACCCCCACACUUCCACUCCACCUCACACCUGUUGGUCCUGCUUUGUGGGUGAUUGAUUGAUACCCAAGGACUGCCCCACCUUUAAAUUCCUGCAAUUUAUGCUGCAACCAACAUCUUAGUGUUUGCUCUCUCCGGGAAGAGGCCAGGUGGGGGAGAACAUACGGUCCAGAGCCUGAGAUCGCCUGGCUGGGGUGCAGGCAAGCAGGAACCCAGUCUAGAUAGAAUGCAGUGUUCUCUAAAGCUAUGGAUGGUUUCAGUGAAAUGUCUGUGUCUGACAAUCGUCACGCAAGAGUACUUACUGUCUUCCCUUGUACAUACAUUGUCUGUGUUUAGCUUUUCCUAGUAUUGUGAGGUUUCAAAUAGGGGUUCCAUGUAAAUACUCUUUCUGCUACUGAAAUGCCGGCCCCCUUGAGUAUGCAUCACCCCCACAGAUGGUUUUGCCUUUCUCUAUGCUAACACUUUUUGAGCCACUGACGUGCAGAUCGGUGGUUAGUUUCUUGGGCUUUUAUUUUGCAAUUUUAUAUAUAUACACAUAUUAUAUAUAUAUAUAUAUUUAUGGGUUGGUUUUGUAUAGUUUUCUGUUUGAAUCUCUGAGCACCAAAGCUGCCCUUUGAUUUUCACGAGAACUUUCCAAAGCCACUUCCUGAGCCCUCCUGCUGCUUUGGUGUCUGACGGUGAUGCUGCGGUGGCAUCUCUGCCCGUGAAUUUCUGUAUGUGUGUGCUGUUACCUCACCUGCAGACAUGACCCUAGUAAAUCUAACGUGCUUGGCUUCCCA